GUAUUUUGGGUCCGGCCUGCUCGCCGUCCGCUCCGUCCGCCCUUAGACCUGUUGCCCAGCAUCCCUGCAGUUCGCGGUACAGUCUCUAGUAGAGCGCGUGUAUAGAGGCAGAGAGGAGUGAAGUCCACAGUUCCUCUCCUCCAAGAGCCUGCCGACCAUGCCCGCGGGCGUGCCCAUGUCCACCUACCUGAAAAUGUUCGCAGCCAGUCUCCUGGCCAUGUGCGCAGGGGCAGAAGUGGUGCACAGGUACUACCGACCGGACCUGGUGAGUGCGGGAGGGCUACUAUUUUAUUUUUGAGCUAAAUAUACCUCAUUUCUUUGUAAAUUACCCAGCCUUAGGCAUUCCUUUAUAGCAAUGCAGAUGCUCCUGGACCACUCCAUUCUCCUCGUGGCAGCAAAAGUGAUCUUGAACGAAAUUAGGAUCACAUUUGCCCUGGGCCCAAAACCUUUGGAUGGCAUCCCAUUGCAUCUAGGGCAAUGCAUGGCCUGUGAGGUCUUACACAGUCUGGCCGCUGCCUACCUGUGGCCUAUCUGCCACCAUUUUACCAGUUCUUUCCCCUGUUAACAUUCACGCCUGCUUCCUUGCUGUUUCUCCAACUCAUCAAACCUGUCCCCAUUUCGAGGCCAUUCUUUUCAUUAUCCUUGGCAUGUCCUCCUCCCCCCACCACCCCCCCAACAACUUGGCUUGGUUUCCUUCUUCAAAACUUCAAGUCUUAGCACAAGUCUCUCCUCCAGCAAUGAGGGUCCUUGGGUUAGCUCCCAAAGAAUUCCUCCUCUGCGAUUCCGUCUCAUCUUUUGUUUCCAUAGAGCACUUGUCUGCAGUUCUUUGUCUAUUUAUUUGUUCUUUGUCAGUUUGCUUCAGUAGAAUGUAAGCUCCAGACUAUGUCUGUCUGGUUCAGUCUUGUAUCUCAACUGCUUGGAAUGUAGCAGACACUCAAUAAGUAUUUGUUGAAUGAAGGAUGAGUGACUAUAGGCAUUCAAAGGAAGGAGAAAUUUAAAUUAAUUUUAAUAAGCAUUCAUUAGGAACUAGAAUUAAAGGUUCUUUUCAGGAAUUAGAGUCUUGGGGAGGUGGAGAUGAGAAAGUAUGGCACAAAUAAUUACAAGAAUGUGCUGUUAUGCUAUAGGUGUGAAUAGUGGUUUGGAGCACAAUGUUGGGAGCAGUCAUUUCUGUUUGGACUCUGCCUGGACAGAUGAGAAACAGGUUGAGAAGAGUGAAGUUGAUUUCUCAAAGUCACAUAGCUUAGUGAGACGAUUUGAGGAUCUGAAGCCCAAGCUUUCUGUUUGCAAAACUGGAUCACAAGUCUUUCGGUCGGAGAACUGGAAGGUCUGGGCAGAGUCGAGCAGAGGAGACCAUGAUGACUGCCUAGACUUGUGCUCAGUGCUGUGUUGGGGAGAACUGCUACAGACAAUACCUGAAAUUCCACCAAAGCGUGGAGAACUCAAAACGGAGCUUUUGGGACUGAAAGAAAGAAAACACAAACCUCAAGUUUCUCAACAGGAGGAACUUAAAUAACUAUGCCAAGAAUUCUGUGAAUAAUAUAAGUCUUAAAUAUGUAUUUCUUAAUUUAUUGCAUCAAACUACUUGUCCUUAAGCACUUAGUCUAAUGCUAACUGCAAGAGGAGGUGCUCAGUGGAUGUUUAGCCGAUACGUUGAAAUUUAAUUACGGUUUGAUUGAUAUUUCUUGAAAACUGCCAAAGCACAUAUCAUCAAACCAUUUCAUGAAUAUGGUUUGGAAGAUGUUUAGUCUUGAAUAUAACGCGAAAUAGAAUAUUUGUAAGUCUACUAUAUGGGUUGUCUUUAUUUCAUAUAAAUUAAGAAAUUAUUUAAAACUAUGAACUAGUUUCAUUAAUUGAAUUUGCUAAGUGGAGUUAUUUCUCAUUGCUAAACUGUUUUUUUUCAAAUUCUAGAUCUCUGCUAACUUUAGUAAAUGAACACUAAAGUGGUGAGCUUUGAUAAUGCAUUUUGUGGAUACAAAAUCAUCGCCUCAUCACUUUCUAGAAUGAAAGGCUGGGGGCAUUGCUCACCUUUUGCGUGAAGAAAAGACCUGUCCCUUAGAGCCAGUUUUUGCUUAAGGGGAGGACAGACCGUCGUCACCCAGUGGACCACGUGAAUGAAUGGAUGCAGUGCAUGCUUUAGAAGCACCGCAUACCUCCUUUUACAGGUACAGAGUAAGUGGUCUGGCUACUGAGGGAAAGAGUCAUGAUUUGAAUCCGAGUCUUCUGUAAGACAAUGACUUCAUGAAGGUGAAAAAUCAGUUUUAUGGUUAUUAAAGUAAAAAUUUACCUUGGGUAAAAAUGCCAUCUUUAUUUCAUUAAGUACUGGUUCUAAGUGACUUCCAAUAAGAUACAUUUUCUUCCUGUUUUGAAGUUGAUCCCCAUUGUGAAAAAUAUACAUUGUAGUGGUCAUGGAAAUGCGCCAUCCAUACUCCCUAAGGCAGGCUUGUUGCCCUAGUAUCAAGCAUGCCAGCAGCUUUCAAUGGUCAGCUUCUAGAAGGAUUGCCUCGGCUAUGGUGGCCUUGCUCAAAGCCAUGCCUCCUGAAGGGGCCCAAAUCCAGUGACUGUUGGAGGUGAGAAUAGAAAGGCCUGGCCACUUCAGCACGUGAGUGGUGGGCAACUCUGCUGGGCCCACCACAACUCCCUAUGGGGUUUAGGGACACUGUCUUUGGAUCUGCAUUGCAACUCAACUUAUACCUCUGCUCAGUCCUGUUUCCUUUCUCAGGUGUUGAUCGAAGGGUGUGCCUUCAUAGACCCCCUGCUAAACUGCACCUCAGUGUUUCUUGGAGAACCAAAUCUGUAACAUAUAUGCAUUAAAAAUUAAAGGCAGUACUAUAUUAUCCCCUAA